AGCAGCCCCUGUCCAGUCUUCCCCCGACCAUCCCUCAGAGAGCCAUGUACAGUUCUCAGAGCCCUGUGGUGGCUCUGCUGCCUUCACGAUCACUUCCCCCCAAAGCUGGCCCCAGCAGGCCCCCCAGAGUUGGGUCCCUUCUCAGCUCUUAAGCCUCAUUGCCCCCAUUCCACCUCUUUACCCCCGCUUCUGCCAAACCAAACCCUUGAGCGCCUCCUCAGCCUUCACAUUGCUCCAUGCCCCAACCUUCAUACUGCUGGCCUUCUUCCAGAACAUUCUCUCCCCAUCAUCAUGACUCUCCAUUGAGAGAGCUCUGCCUGCUACCCCUUCCUGCCCUGCUGGGCCCCUCAUGCCUCCAUCGCAUUAUUGUGUGAAUGGCUAAUGUCCCCUCCUUGAUGGGGCCAUCUCUGAGGAUAGGGACGUGGCCCUAGUGCAGAGAUGCUCAGGGAUGUUUAGGGAAGGAAGUCAUCAAGAGACCUAGAUGUGAACCCCAUCCAUAGCGCCUCCCAAACCAUGUGGUCUUGGCCUCCCUGGGCUUUGAUUCCCUCAUCAGUCCUGCCUGCGCUGCCAGGCUUCUGUGAGCCUUUAAUGAGCCUGUGUUGACAGAUGAAUGCAUUCUUGGGACUACUAAUCAACGCAUACAACUAAGGCCAAGAGAAGCCAGGGUUUCUACCCCAGGGACCCCCUUGGCCCCACCCUCUAGCCCUGGAGCUGGGUCCCUCUGCCUCUCCCAGGAUGCAGUCAGAGGCCUGAGCUUCUGGAAACUCUUGGAUCUCGUCCCUGCUCCUCCCAGUCCCACCUCGGCUCCAGGUGUCUAUCUCUCCAGCUAUUUUCUUUUCUGAUCUGGAGUUCAAAAGAACAGAUCUAGGAGCAACAGCCACGGGGAACAACAGCCAGCAGGCUAGUUCAUGUUGGCCCAGCUGAGAGCCUGCGGGGCUGCCCACCUCUCCCUGCUGGGUUUGGGCACCCAGAAAGGAGGGCGUAUGGGUUCUGGUUCUAUGGGCAUUAAAAGCCAAUGUGACUGAGAACAGCAGCUCUAGUUAGAGGCAAGGCCAGUUUGGGGCCAGAGCAGGGGGAGGGGGAACCUGGUCUAAUUAGAGCCCUAACAUGCUCCUUUGAAAGCAUUGUCAGAUGUCCCCAGCCCUGCAGGCAGGGGUGGUGUAAUAAUAAUAAAACAACAUUUGCAUAGAGAUUUCAUUUAUAAAGCACUUUCUCAGGGGUGGGGUGGCACUGGGUGGCCCUGUGGAAUCCUGGCUGGGAGGCCGCCCUGGCCUUGGUCGGUUCCGCCCUCCCGCCAAGCUGGCGAUUGUGUGCGAGGUAAACAAAGCGCCAUUCAUCCAACUGUUUCAGUUCCUCUCCUCUUCAUUCCUUUUUCCCUGUCUCCCACGAAGAGCUCACUCGGGGCUUGUCACUCAGGCCAGAAAAGGGGUGUCAGGGGCCCCAGAGGGAGACCCCUUCCCUCAUGGGAAGAAGCGGGGAGGUGGGACGGCUCCCUCCCUCUGCAAACCCCCACCACCCCCAGCUCUGGCAGAAUAACAGCCUUGCUGCGGUUGGUUUGUGCAACUCUUUGCUAACCUGUGGCUGUGUCUUCAUGGACAAAGUAUGAGCCCAGGUUUGGUAAUGUCUGUGUGCACGCCACGUUUGUGUUCGGUAACAUGCAAAGAUAAGCAGUUUGUGGGGCUCUGCGAAUCCCUCCCUAUCCGAGUGAGCCUUGUGUACACAGUGUGGGGGUGAGGGGCCCUGGGGUGUCUGCCCCUGCACUGGGUGGGCCGGGUGAGGCAGCUGGGCCCUGCUCCUGUACAGCCCAGGCUGGAGCGUCCCCUGCAGUCACCUGGCCACUGGCACCCUGGGGUGAAGGGGGAGGCAUUGGGCGCUGGCCCCUUAAGGGCCUCUGAUGAGCUAUAUUGGGCCCACCUGCCUGGGUUCCAGCAGCUUCCGCAGCCCCAGCAGGAGACGGAAGAUGCAAGAGGUCAUUGCGGGGCUAGAGCGGUUCACCUUUGCCUUCGAGAAGGAUGUCGAGAUGCAGAAGGGCACUGGGCUCCUGCCUUUCCAGGGCAUGGACAAGUCGGCCUCAGCUGUGUGCAACUUCUUCACUAAAGGGCUCUGUGAGAAAGGGAAACUCUGCCCCUUCCGACAUGACCGAGGGGAGAAGAUGGUGGUAUGCAAGCACUGGCUCCGGGGGCUCUGCAAGAAGGGUGAUCACUGCAAGUUCCUGCACCAGUAUGACCUCACCAGGAUGCCUGAGUGCUACUUCUACUCCAAGUUUGGUGACUGCAGCAACAAGGAGUGUUCCUUCCUCCAUGUGAAGCCAGCUUUCAAGUCCCAGGACUGUCCUUGGUAUGACCAAGGUUUCUGCAAGGACGGUCCUCUGUGUAAAUACCGCCAUGUCCCCAGAAUAAUGUGUCUCAACUAUUUAGUUGGCUUCUGCCCCGAGGGACCCAAGUGCCAAUUUGCUCACCUUGCUUAACAGCCCGAAGAGAAACUUUUCCAAAUGCCCAGAACCUGCAACAGAAGACAACAGUCAAACUCCAGCCUCACCUUUUUGUACAGCUCCCAAGAGCCUCAUUAGAGAGAAGUUGGAGGUUGUAAGUCCGGCAGGGGGUUCCAAACUCCUUAUAUGAGUUGAGCUUCGUUCCAACAAAGAAACUAUGGUUCCAAACAGAAGUCACUGUCAUUGUUUACCGAAACGUACCCCCUUCCCUAACAUCCAGUGCCGAAGGAUCCACGGCUAAGCCUCAGGAAGAGCAUAUUCUAAACAGGUGCAUUAAAGAUUUCUGCAUUGGACUGCA